AGUGUUCGGCUGGGGCAGGCACGCUGUGGCUGGCUACUUCCCUUCCUCCCAUCCCCCUUGGGCCAAACGGGAUCGGUGCUUCUGGUGAGACGCCUCCCCAUGCACAUCACUCCCAGGUGCCCUAGGGGGCACAUUUCCCACAACUCCCAGAGGGCAGGUUUCUAGAAAGUGCCACCAGUGGGGAGGCGCCACAACUUCACUGCCAUUUUGUGAGGUGCCGCCGUCUCUCCUCCAGCAAGGAAACAAUGACCGAUAAAACAGAGAAGGUGGCUGUAGAUCCUGAAACUGUGUUUAAACGUCCCAGGGAAUGUGACAGUCCUUCGUAUCAGAAAAGGCAGAGGAUGGCCCUGUUGGCAAGGAAACAAGGAGCAGGAGACAGCCUUAUUGCAGGCUCUGCCAUGUCCAAAGAAAAGAAGCUUAUGACAGGACAUGCUAUUCCACCCAGCCAAUUGGAUUCUCAGAUUGAUGACUUCACUGGUUUCAGCAAAGAUGGGAUGAUGCAGAAACCUGGUAGCAAUGCACCUGUGGGAGGAAACGUUACCAGCAGUUUCUCUGGAGAUGACCUAGAAUGCAGAGAAACAGCCUCCUCUCCCAAAAGCCAACGAGAAAUUAAUGCUGAUAUAAAACGUAAAUUAGUGAAGGAACUCCGAUGCGUUGGACAAAAAUAUGAAAAAAUCUUCGAAAUGCUUGAAGGAGUGCAAGGACCUACUGCAGUCAGGAAGCGAUUUUUUGAAUCCAUCAUCAAGGAAGCAGCAAGAUGUAUGAGACGAGACUUUGUUAAGCACCUUAAGAAGAAACUGAAACGUAUGAUUUGAGAAUACUUGUCCCUGGAGGAUUAUCACACCCCAAAUGCAUAAUCUCGUUAAUGAUUGAGGAGAGAAAAGGAUCAGAUUGCUGUUUUCUACAAUGGAGCAGGAUAUUGCUGAAGUCUCCUGGCAUAUGUUACCGAAUCAACUGGCCUUCCAGAGGCUAAGAAAUUUCUGUUAGUAAAAGAUGUUCUUUUUCCCAAAGCGUUUUAUUUGAAAG